GUUAUCUCCCUGAGCAACCUGUGGAAAGCCGCUGAGCAACCUGUGGAAAGCCGCUGAGCGGUUAUCCUCUCGGGGCAUAAAGACAAAGAAGGCAAUAAGGAGACUUUGCUCCUCAGAGGCCACCCGUGGCUUCCCAUGGGUGUCUCACACAGGGGAGACCAACUCAACUGGCACCUAGAACUCUCUUUCCCACAAAAGCUAGGCUGGUUCUGAUUCUUAACCUGCUCCAGCAGUGACACACUCAGUCCCACAGGGAGUGGACGACCCCCAGGAAGAAGAUGAUGUUUUGGAGGAAACUCCCCAAAGCCCUCUUCAUUGGGCUGACUCUGGCCAUUGCUGUCAAUCUCCUUCUGGUAUUUUCUAGCAAGGGGACUUUACAAAACCUGUUUACGGGUGGUCUCCACAGGGAGCUUCCUUUACAUCUGAAUAAACGCUACGGGGCAGUGAUAAAGAGACUCUCCCACUUGGAGGUGGAAUUGCAGGAUCUGAAAGAAAGUAUGAAAUUAGCUCUGAGGCAACAAGAAAAUGUGAACAGCACACUGAAGAGGGCGAAAGAUGAAGUACGCCCUCUUCUAAAGGCAAUGGAAACCAAGGUGAAUGAGACAAAGAAGCACAAAACCCAAAUGAAACUCUUCCCACACUCACAGCUUUUCAGGCAAUGGGGCGAGGAUCUUUCUGAGGCCCAGCAGAAGGCGGCCCAGGACCUCUUCCGGAAGUUUGGUUACAACGCGUACCUCAGCAACCAGCUGCCUCUCAAUCGCACCAUCCCCGACACGCGAGACUACAGAUGUCUUCGGAAGACAUAUCCUUCCCAACUCCCAUCCCUCAGUGUCAUUCUCAUAUUCGUGAAUGAAGCUCUGUCCAUUAUACAACGGGCCAUCACCAGUAUCAUCAACCGGACGCCCUCUCGAUUGUUGAAGGAAAUCAUCUUGGUGGAUGAUUUCAGCUCAAAUGGAGAACUAAAGGUACACUUGGAUGAGAAGAUUAAGCUUUACAACCAGAAGUAUCCAGGACUACUGAAAAUAAUACGGCAUCCUGAAAGGAAAGGUCUUGCUCAAGCCCGCAACACUGGCUGGGAAGCUGCCACAGCAGACGUGGUCGCCAUCUUGGAUGCUCACAUUGAAGUCAAUGUUGGGUGGGCAGAGCCAAUCUUGGCUCGGAUUCAGGAGGACCGCACUGUGAUUGUGUCUCCUGUGUUUGACAACAUUCGUUUUGACACCUUCAAACUGGAUAAGUAUGAACUGGCAGUUGAUGGGUUUAACUGGGAACUCUGGUGCCGCUACGAUGCACUGCCACAAGCCUGGAUUGAUCUGCAUGAUGUCACUGCCCCAGUGAAGAGUCCUUCAAUCAUGGGCAUCCUGGCUGCUAACAGGCACUUCCUGGGAGAGAUCGGGUCUCUGGAUGGUGGAAUGCUCAUCUAUGGAGGAGAGAACGUGGAGCUUAGCCUGAGGGUGUGGCAGUGUGGAGGGAAGGUCGAGAUUUUGCCCUGUUCCCGGAUUGCCCACCUAGAGAGACACCACAAGCCCUACGCCUUGGAUCUCACCGCUGCCUUGAAGCGCAAUGCUCUGCGAGUGGCCGAAAUCUGGAUGGAUGAGCACAAACACAUGGUCUACUUGGCCUGGAACAUACCUCUCCAGAACUCUGGAAUAGAUUUUGGAGACGUUUCUUCCAGAAUGGCACUCCGGGAAAAACUGAAAUGUAAAACUUUUGACUGGUACCUGAAAAAUGUUUAUCCACUCUUGAAGCCACUCCACACCAUCGUGGGCUAUGGAAGAAUGAAAAACCUAUUGGAUGAAAAUGUCUGCUUGGAUCAGGGACCCGUUCCAGGCAACACCCCCAUCAUGUAUUACUGCCAUGAAUUCAGCUCACAGAAUGUCUACUAUCACCUAACUGGGGAGCUCUAUGUGGGACAACUGAUUGCAGAGGCCAGUGCUAGUGAUCGCUGCCUGACAGACCCUGGCAAGGCGGAGAAGCCCACCUUAGAACCAUGCUCCAAGGCAGCUAAGAAUAGACUGCAUAUAUAUUGGGAUUUUAAACCGGGAGGAGCUGUCAUAAACAGAGAUACCAAGCGGUGUCUGGAGAUGAAGAAGGAUCUUUUGGGUAGCCACGUGCUUGUGCUCCAGACCUGUAGCACGCAAGUGUGGGAAAUCCAGCACACUGUCAGAGACUGGGGUCAGACCAACAGCCAGUGAUCCUCAGAUGGUGCUGGAUCUGGGUCAUCAAUUCUUGCAAGUGGAAUGGCUUCUACUCCUAACACUCCCAGCUUCUUUCUCAAUGAGAAAGAAAGCAUGUGUAUGUCUGUUUAUGGCGACUUCAGGUGG